AUUUGGAGCAUUUCCUUCCCUGACAGCCGGACCUGGGACUGGGCUGGGGCCCUGGCGGAUGGAGACAUGCUGCCCCUGCUGCUGCUGCCCCUGCUGUGGGGGGGGUCCCUGCAGGAGAAGCCAGUGUACGAGCUGCAAGUGCAGAAGUCGGUGACGGUGCAGGAGGGCCUGUGCGUCCUUGUGCCCUGCUCCUUCUCUUACCCCUGGAGAUCCUGGUAUUCCUCUCCCCCACUCUACGUCUACUGGUUCCGGGACGGGGAGAUCCCAUACUACGCUGAGGUUGUGGCCACAAACAACCCAGACAGAAGAGUGAAGCCAGAGACCCAGGGCCGAUUCCGCCUCCUUGGGGAUGUCCAGAAGAAGAACUGCUCCCUGAGCAUCGGAGAUGCCAGAAUGGAGGACACGGGAAGCUAUUUCUUCCGCGUGGAGAGAGGAAGGGAUGUAAAAUAUAGCUACCAACAGAAUAAGCUGAACUUGGAGGUGACAGCCCUGAUAGAGAAACCCGACAUCCACUUUCUGGAGCCUCUGGAGUCCGGCCGCCCCACAAGGCUGAGCUGCAGCCUUCCAGGAUCCUGUGAAGCGGGACCACCUCUCACAUUCUCCUGGACGGGGAAUGCCCUCAGCCCCCUGGACCCCGAGACCACCCGCUCCUCGGAGCUCACCCUCACCCCCAGGCCCGAGGACCAUGGCACCAACCUCACCUGUCAGGUGAAACGCCAAGGAGCUCAGGUGACCACGGAGAGAACUGUCCAGCUCAAUGUCUCCUAUGCUCCACAGAACCUCGCCAUCAGCAUCUUCUUCAGAAAUGGCACAGGCACAGCCCUGCGGAUCCUGAGCAAUGGCAUGUCGGUGCCCAUCCAGGAGGGCCAGUCCCUGUUCCUCGCCUGCACAGUUGACAGCAACCCCCCUGCCUCACUGAGCUGGUUCCGGGAGGGAAAAGCCCUCAAUCCUUCCCAGACCUCAAUGUCUGGGACCCUGGAGCUGCCUAACAUAGGAGCUAGAGAGGGAGGGGAAUUCACCUGCCGGGUUCAGCAUCCGCUGGGCUCCCAGCACCUGUCCUUCAUCCUUUCUGUGCAGAGAAGCUCCUCUUCCUGCAUAUGUGUAACUGAGAAACAGCAGGGCUCCUGGCCCCUCGUCCUCACCCUGAUCAGGGGGGCUCUCAUGGGGGCUGGCUUCCUCCUCACCUAUGGCCUCACCUGGAUCUACUAUACCAGGUGUGGAGGCCCCCAGCAGAGCAGGGCUGAGAGGCCUGGCUGAGCCCCUCCCGCUCAAGACAGAACUGAGGUGUGGACACUUAGCCCUGUGGGACACAUGCAGGACAUCACUGUCAGCUUCUUUCUGGAAGCUCACAUCCCACUGACUACCCCUCUUUUCCUUCCUGCCCCAUACCCCUUCUACUUAUUCCCCUCUGCUUGUGAGUCUUGCCCCACCACACCUGCAUCCCCAUCUGCACCCCAUCCCCUCUCCACCUGCCCUUCUCUUCCCUCUCCAUCCACCAUCUCCAGCCCUGUGAAGGGAAUGUACUUUCGGUCUUAUACCCCCAUUACCCAUUACCCAAAAGUUACCUUUUUUUUUUUUUUUUUUUUUUGAGACAGAGUCUCACUCUGUUGCACAGGCUGGAGUUCAGUGGCACAAUCUCCGUUCACUGCAACCUCCACCUCUGGGGUUCAAGCAAUUCUCCUGCCUCAGCCUCCCUAGUAGCUGGGAUUACAGGUGCCUGCCACCACAUCCAGUUAAUUUUUUUUUUUUGUAUGUUAGUAGAGAUGGGGUUUUACCAUGUUGGCCAGGUCUCGAACUCCUGACCUCAAGCAAUCCACUGCAUUGGCCUCCCAAAGUGCUGGCAUUACAGGUAUGAGCCACCGUGCCUGGCUGCCAAAAGUUACCUUCUUAACACUUGAAUUUCUGGUCUCCUCAGCUUCCCUAUCCAUAUAGGCACAGAGAGGCAGCAUUUGUUUUCCAGUUAAAACUCUACCUCAUUGUGAUUAUUAUCCAAUACAAUUGUUACAAAAUAAGUAAAACUUUUAUGAAACAAUACAACAUAACUGAUUUUACUCUUUAAUGCCUCUGUGAGAGUUUGUAGACAAAAAUUAUGUCUUUUUUUUUUUUCUUUGAGACAGAGUUUCUAUCUUGUUGCCCAGGCUGGAGUGCAAUGGCAAAAUCUCAGCUCACUGCAACUUCUGCCUCCCAGGUUCAAGUGAUUCUCCUUCUGUCCAUAUACAAGAAGGCAAUACCUGUAUUGUCAGGUUCUGUGCAUCGUAUAACUGGAACCAAACAUAUUUGCUUUAGGGUCUGCUUUCAUUUCUUCAGUGUGGUUUUCCCAGUUUAUCCACGUUGUUACACGUAUCAAUAGCUCAUUCUCAGUUUUGGUGGGGUUUUUUUUGCUUUUAAUAUCGUACAGUCAGCCUUCUGUAUCCACUGGUUCUGCAUUUUCCCUUUAAUCACUUUUGCUGCACCACAAAAGUUUUGUUAUGUUGUAUUUUUAUAUUAGUUCAAAAUAUUUCCUUCUUUCCCCUGAGAUUUCCUUUGAAUUCACGGAUUGCUUAGAAGUGUGUUGUUUAAUUUCUAAGUGAUUGCAGAUUUUACUGGUUUUUUAUUUUUAAACAAAUUGUUACUACUUUCUUUUUAAGUUCCAUUUUAAUAAAUACACAUGCUUGAUAUGAUUUUUUUUAACUUUUAAGUUCAGGGGGCACAAGUGCAGGUUUGUUACAUAGGUAAAGUGUCAUGGGAGUUUGUUGUACAGAUUAUUGCAUCACCCAGAUAUUAAGCCUAGUACCCAUUAGUUAUUUUCCUCAUCCUCUCCCUCCUCCCACCUUCCACCCUUUGAAAGGCCCCAGUGUGUGUUGCUCACCUCUAUGUAUCCAUGUGUUCUCAUCAUUUAGCUCCCACUUACAAGUGAGAACAUGUGGUAUUUGGUUUUCUCUUCUUGUGAUAGUUUGCUGAGGAUAAUGGUCUCCAGCUCCACUCAUGUCCCUGCAAAGGACAUAAUCUCAUUCUUUUUUAUGGCUGCUUAGUAUUCCAUGGUGUAUAUGUACCACAUUUUCUCUAUCCAGUCUACCACUGAUAGGCAGUUAGGUUGAUUCCAUGUCAUUGCUAUUGUGAAUAGUGCUGCAGUGAAUGUAUGCAUGCAUGUGUCUUUGUAAUAGAAUGAUUUAUAUUCCUUUGGGUAUAUGCCUAGGAAUGGGAUUGCUGAGUCGAAUGGUAUUUCUAUGUUUAGGUCUUUGAGGAAUCGCCACACUGUCUUCCACAAUGGCUGAACUAACUUUCACUUUCACCAACCGUGAGAGUCUUUUAUAUUGGUUAAGUUUGCUUGAUGACACUGGUCUAUCUUGGUGAAUGCUCCAUGUGUGCUUAGAAAGAAUGUGUAUUGCCCUGUUAUGGGACGAAUAUUAAAUGGCAAUUAGACAUAGUUGUCCAAUGGUGUUCAGUUUUAUAGCUGGUAACUUUUUUGUCUACCAGCUCAGUCUAUUACUGAGAGAGGAAUGUUGAAGUCUCUGAUCCUAAUGUUGGAUUUGUCAGUUUCUCCUCUCAGUUUCAUCAGUUUUUGCUGCAUGUAUUUUUAAACUCUGUCGUUAGGUGCAUACAUAUUAAGAAUUCUCAUGUCUUCUUAAAGAAUCAACUUAAAAAAAAUUUUUUUUUGAGACAGAGUUUCGCUCUUUUUGCCCAGGCUGGAGUGCAAUGGCGCGAUCUUGGCUCACUGCAACCUCCGCCUCCCAGGUACAAGUGAUUCUCCUGCCUCAGCCUCCCAAAUAGCUUGGAUUACAGGCACGCACCAUCACGCCUGGCUAGUUUUUUUUGUAUUUAGUAGAGACAAGGUUUCACCAUGUAAGUCAGGCUGGUCCUGAACUCCUGACUUCAGGUGAUCCACCCGCCUCAGCCUCCAAAGUGCUGGGAUUAUAGGCGUGAGCCACCGCAGUUGGCUGAAUCAACUGUUUUACAUUAUGUAACAUCACUUUUUGUUCCUGUGAUUUUCUUUGCUCUUAAGUGUACUUUGUCUGCUAUUAACAUAGCCAUUCCAGUUUUCUUUUGACUAGUAUUUGCAUAGUAUGCAUUUUCACAUCCUUUAAGUCCUAGCCUCACCUCAUUAUAUUUGAAAUGGAAAGCAUUUAUACUCAGAAGCUGGAGUUCCUUUUCCCUAGCUCUUCCCUUUCCAGAAUUGUUACCUGUUGUUUCAGUGUUCCUAGUUGCCCUGGGCUUCAUCCCUUGUUUCUCAGUCCAGAAAGAUGGAAGGAGUUGUAUUAGAAUUUUAGCAGCCACUUUCUGCACUGUAGCUCUGACCUACCAUUGGAAUAAAGCUAUUUAUUCCUUGUUGGUGCCUUUCCCCAAAUAUUGACUCCCGUUCCAGAAUCUAUUUUCUUUUAUCCCAUUUCCCAAGUAGUUUUUUUUCCCCAUUCAAAGCUUAUAACUUGUAAGGAUUUUUUGUUUGUUUGUUUUGUUGUGUUGUGGUGAGUUCACUCUGCUAGGAGCUUACUCCUUCAUAAUAAAAGCACGACUCCUUCUCUUUCGUUUUGAAGGAUAAUUUUCCAAAAUGUAGAAUUCUAGCUUUGCAUUUUUCUUUUAACCUUUUGGAGAUGUCAUUCCACUUUGGAGGGCGGGUGAGUUUCUCAUGACAAUUCAGUCAUCAUUUUCUUAUUGUGGUUCCAUUUAAGGCAAUAUCUGUUUAUGUCUUGCUGCUUUUAUAAUUUCUUCAUUCUUUUUCAUGAAUUUAACUUUUAUAAACUUCAGGUGUUUUUCUUUUAAUUUCCCUAAGUGCAUGUAGCAAAGAGAGUGCAAUAUUUGCUUUUUUUCUAUAUGCUUUAACUCUUGAUAUACUUUAUUUAUGCUAUAAUAGAAAUGUGUGUCUUCCCAAAAUUUAUAUGUUGAAAUCUUAAACCUCAAGGUGAUGGUAUUAAAAGGUUGGGGCUUUUUGGAAAGUGAUUAACCCAUAAUGGUGCCAUCCUUCAUGAAUGGGAUUAGUGUUCUCAUAAAAGAAACAGAAGGAAGUGUGUUUUCCUCUUCUGCCAUGUGAGGAUACCACGAAAAGAUACUAUCUGGGAAGCAAAUAAUUCUCUCCAGACACUGAAUCCGCUGGCACCUUGAUCUUGGACUUCCCGACCUCCAGAAUUAUGAGAAAUAAAUUUCUGUUGUUUAUAAAUCA